ACUGCAGCUCCCUGAGCACUCUCUACAGAGACGCGGACCCCAGACAUGAGGAGGCUCCUCCUGGUCACCAGCCUGGUGGUUGUGCUGCUGUGGGAGGCAGGUGCAGUCCCAGCACCCAAGGUCCCUAUCAAGAUGCAAGUCAAACACUGGCCCUCAGAGCAGGACCCAGAGAAGGCCUGGGGCGCCCGUGUGGUGGAGCCUCCGGAGAAGGACGACCAGCUGGUGGUGCUGUUCCCUGUCCAGAAGCCGAAACUCUUGACCACCGAGGAGAAGCCACGAGGUCAGGGCAGGGGCCCCAUCCUUCCAGGCACCAAGGCCUGGAUGGAGACCGAGGACACCCUGGGCCAUGUCCUGAGUCCCGAGCCCGACCAUGACAGCCUGUACCACCCUCCGCCUGAGGAGGACCAGGGCGAGGAGAGGCCCCGGUUGUGGGUGAUGCCAAAUCACCAGGUGCUCCUGGGACCGGAGGAAGACCAAGACCACAUCUACCACCCCCAGUAGGGCUCCAGGGGCCAUCACUGCCCCCGCCCUGUCCCAAGGCCCAGGCUGUUGGGACUGGGACCCUCCCUACCCUGCCCCAGCUAGACAAAUAAACCCCAGCAGGCCGGGCGCGGUGGCUCACCUCUGUAAUCCCAGCACUUUUAGAGGCCGAGGCAGGCGGAUCACCUGAAAUCAGGAGUUCCAGACCAGCCUGGGCAACAUGGUGAAACCCCGUCUCUACUAAAAAUACAAAAAUUAGCCGGG